CUCUUCCGAAUGUCCUGCGGCCCCAGCCUCUCCUCACGCUCGCGCAGUCUCCGCCGCAGUCUCAGCUGCAGCUGCAGGACUGAGCCGUGCACCCGGAGGAGACCCCCGGAGGAGGCGACAAACUUCGCAGUGCCGCGACCCAACCCCAGCCCUGGGUAGCCUGCAGCAUGGCCCAGCUGUUCCUGCCCCUGCUGGCAGCCCUGGUCCUGGCCCAGGCUCCUGCAGCUUUAGCAGAUGUUCUGGAAGGAGACAGCUCAGAGGACCGCGCUUUUCGCGUGCGCAUCGCGGGCGACGCGCCACUGCAGGGCGUGCUCGGCGGCGCCCUCACCAUCCCUUGCCACGUCCACUACCUGCGGCCACCGCCGAGCCGCCGGGCUGUGCUGGGCUCUCCGCGGGUCAAGUGGACUUUCCUGUCCCGGGGCCGGGAGGCAGAGGUGCUGGUGGCGCGGGGAGUGCGCGUCAAGGUGAACGAGGCCUACCGGUUCCGCGUGGCACUGCCUGCGUACCCAGCGUCGCUCACCGACGUCUCCCUGGCGCUGAGCGAGCUGCGCCCCAACGACUCAGGUAUCUAUCGCUGUGAGGUCCAGCACGGCAUCGAUGACAGCAGCGACGCUGUGGAGGUCAAGGUCAAAGGGGUCGUCUUUCUCUACCGAGAGGGCUCUGCCCGCUAUGCUUUCUCCUUUUCUGGGGCCCAGGAGGCCUGUGCCCGCAUUGGAGCCCACAUCGCCACCCCGGAGCAGCUCUAUGCCGCCUACCUUGGGGGCUAUGAGCAAUGUGAUGCUGGCUGGCUGUCGGAUCAGACCGUGAGGUAUCCCAUCCAGACCCCACGAGAGGCCUGUUACGGAGACAUGGAUGGCUUCCCCGGGGUCCGGAACUAUGGUGUGGUGGACCCGGAUGACCUCUAUGAUGUGUACUGUUAUGCUGAAGACCUAAAUGGAGAACUGUUCCUGGGUGACCCUCCAGAGAAGCUGACAUUGGAGGAAGCACGGGCGUACUGCCAGGAGCGGGGUGCAGAGAUUGCCACCACGGGCCAACUGUAUGCAGCCUGGGAUGGUGGCCUGGACCACUGCAGCCCAGGGUGGCUAGCUGAUGGCAGUGUGCGCUACCCCAUCGUCACACCCAGCCAGCGCUGUGGUGGGGGCUUGCCUGGUGUCAAGACUCUCUUCCUCUUCCCCAACCAGACUGGCUUCCCCAAUAAGCACAGCCGCUUCAACGUCUACUGCUUCCGAGACUCGGCCCAGCCUUCUGCCAUCCCUGAGGCCUCCAACCCAGCCUCCAACCCAGCCUCUGAUGGACUAGAGGCUAUCGUCACAGUGACAGAGACCCUGGAGGAACUGCAGCUGCCUCAGGAAGCCACAGAGAGUGAAUCCCGUGGGGCCAUCUACUCCAUCCCCAUCAUGGAGGACGGAGGAGGUGGAAGCUCCACUCCAGAAGACCCAGCAGAGGCCCCUAGGACGCUCCUAGAAUUUGAAACACAAUCCAUGGUACCGCCCACGGGGUUCUCAGAAGAGGAAGGUAAGGCAUUGGAGGAAGAAGAGAAAUAUGAAGAUGAAGAAGAGAAAGAGGAGGAAGAAGAAGAGGAGGAGGUGGAGGAUGAGGCUCUGUGGGCAUGGCCCAGCGAGCUCAGCAGCCCGGGCCCUGAGGCCUCUCUCCCCACUGAGCCAGCAGCCCAGGAGGAGUCACUCUCCCAGGCGCCAGCAAGGGCAGUCCUGCAGCCUGGUGCAUCACCACUUCCUGAUGGAGAGUCAGAAGCUUCCAGGCCUCCAAGGGUCCAUGGACCACCUACUGAGACUCUGCCCACUCCCAGGGAGAGGAACCUAGCAUCCCCAUCACCUUCCACUCUGGUUGAGGCAAGAGAGGUGGGGGAGGCAACUGGUGGUCCUGAGCUAUCUGGGGUCCCUCGAGGAGAGAGCGAGGAGACAGGAAGCUCCGAGGGUGCCCCUUCCCUGCUUCCAGCCACACGGGCCCCUGAGGGUACCAGGGAGCUGGAGGCCCCCUCUGAAGAUAAUUCUGGAAGAACUGCCCCAGCAGGGACCUCAGUGCAGGCCCAGCCAGUGCUGCCCACUGACAGCGCCAGCCGAGGUGGAGUGGCCGUGGUCCCCGCAUCAGGUAAUUCUGCCCAAGGCUCAACUGCCCUCUCUAUCCUACUCCUUUUCUUCCCCCUGCAGCUCUGGGUCACCUGACCUGUAGUCCUUUAACCCACCAUCAUCCCAAACUCUCCUGUCCUUUGCCUUCAUUCUCUUACCCACCUCUACCUAUGGGUCUCCAAUCUCGGAUAUCCACCUUGUGGGUAUCUCAGCUCUCCGCGUCUUUACCCUGUGAUCCCAGCCCCGCCACUGACCAUCUGUGACCCUUCCCUGCCAUUGGGCCCUCCACCUGUGGCUCACAUCUCGCCAGCCCCACAGAGCAUCCUCAGGCCUCUCCAAGGGUCCUCAUCACCUAUUGCAGCCUUCAGGGCUCGGCCUAUUUUCCACUACUCCCUUCAUCCGCCUGUGUGCCGUCCCCUUUAGCUGCCUCCUAUUGAUCUCAGGGAAGCCUGGGAGUCCCUUCUCACCCCUCAACCUCCGGAGUCCAGGAGAACCCGUACCCCCA